CCGUGCUGGGCCCCGGUGCACGGCGAUGCUGGCGAUCGCGGCUGGCGGUUGCUGCUCGGCAUGUGACGUCCCGGGCGUUUUUCUACACGCCUCGCAUCCGCGCGUUUCAGAGCCACAGCCCCUGCUUACGCUAGAGCAGCUGAGGGACAGGGAGGCUCAGUAACUUGCUGUUAAUGAGAGGAAUCAUGGUUUGAGCCGAUGGAAUCUGCAGGGCAGACCCCGAGGCUGGGCUGCCUCCCAGAGGAUGAAGCCAACGCACACGAUGGUCAACUGCUGGUUCUGCAACCAGGAUACGCUGGUGCCCUAUGGGAACCGCAACUGCUGGGACUGUCCCCACUGCGAGCAGUACAACGGCUUCCAGGAGAACGGCGACUACAACAAGCCGAUCCCCGCCCAGUACUUGGAGCACCUGAACCACGUGGUGAGCAGCGCGCCCAGCCUGCGCGACCCUUCGCAGCCGCAGCAGUGGGUGAGCAGCCAAGUCCUGCUGUGCAAGAGGUGCAACCACCACCAGACCACCAAGAUCAAGCAGCUGGCCGCCUUCGCUCCCCGCGAGGAGGGCAGGUAUGACGAGGAGGUCGAGGUGUACCGGCAUCACCUGGAGCAGAUGUACAAGCUGUGCCGGCCGUGCCAAGCGGCUGUGGAGUACUACAUCAAGCACCAGAACCGCCAGCUGCGCGCCCUGUUGCUCAGCCACCAGUUCAAGCGCCGGGAGGCCGACCAGACCCACGCACAGAACUUCUCCUCCGCCGUGAAGUCCCCGGUCCAGGUCAUCCUGCUCCGUGCCCUCGCCUUCCUGGCCUGCGCCUUCCUACUGACCACCGCGCUGUAUGGGGCCAGCGGACACUUCGCCCCAGGCACCACUGUGCCCCUGGCCCUGCCACCUGGUGGCAAUGGCUCAGCCACACCUGACAAUGGCACCACCCCUGGGGCCGAGGGCUGGCGGCAGUUGCUGGGCCUACUCCCCGAGCACAUGGCGGAGAAGCUGUGUGAGGCCUGGGCCUUUGGGCAGAGCCACCAGACGGGCGUCGUGGCACUGGGCCUACUCACCUGCCUGCUGGCAAUGCUGCUGGCUGGCCGCAUCAGGCUCCGGAGGAUCGAUGCCUUCUGCACCUGCCUGUGGGCCCUGCUGCUGGGGCUGCACCUGGCUGAGCAGCACCUGCAGGCCGCCUCGCCUAGCUGGCUAGACACGCUCAAGUUCAGCACCACAUCUUUGUGCUGCCUGGUUGGCUUCACGGCGGCUGUGGCCACAAGGAAGGCAACGGGCCCACGGAGGUUCCGGCCCCGAAGGUUCUUCCCAGGAGACUCUGCCGGCCUUUUCCCCACCAGCCCCAGCUUGGCCAUCCCUCACCCGAGUGUCGGAGGCUCUCCAGCGUCUCUGUUCAUCCCCAGCCCGCCCAGCUUCCUGCCCCUCGCCAACCAGCAGCUCUUCCGGUCUCCUCGACGGACCUCACCCUCCUCAUUGCCUGGCCGCCUCAGCCGGGCCCUCUCUCUGGGAACCAUACCCUCUCUGACUCGAGCAGACUCCGGCUAUCUGUUCAGCGGUAGCCGCCCACCAUCUCAGGUGUCUCGAUCUGGGGAGUUUCCUGUUUCAGAUUACUUCUCUCUUCUGUCGGGGAGCUGCCCCUCCUCCCCACUCCCUUCCCCAGCGCCUUCCGUGGCCGGCUCGGUGGCCUCCAGCUCCGGCUCUCUGCGCCACCGCAGGCCCCUCAUCAGCCCUGCCCGGCUCAACCUGAAGGGACAGAAGCUGCUGCUGUUCCCGUCACCCCCUGGAGAGGCCCCCACCACGCCCAGCAGCUCCGAUGAGCACUCGCCUCACAACGGCAGCCUCUUCACCAUGGAGCCGCCCCAUGUUCCCCGGAAGCCGCCCCUGCAGGACGUGAAGCACGCCCUGGUUGACCUUCAGGGUCCUCUGUUUCUUGGAACUGAUCGAAAACACAUCACGCAUUGCCAGAUGCAGUCUCACUCUGUCGCCCAGGCUGGAGUGCAGUGGCGUGAUCUUGGCUCACUGCAACCUCCUCCUCCAGGGUUCAAGAGAUUGUCCUGCUUCAGCCUCCCGAGUAGCUGGGACUACAGACCUGAGAUCCAAGCUGGAAAGAGGCAGUGCCUGCAGCAACCGCUCCAUCAAGAAAGAGGACGACUCUUCCCAGUCAUCUACCUGUGUGGUGGACACCACCACCAGGGGCUGCUCGGAGGAGGCCGCCACCUGGAGAGGUCGUUUCGGCCCUUCCCUGGUCCGGGGCCUCCUGGCCGUGAGCUUGGCCGCCAACGCCCUGUUCACCUCGGUGUUUCUGUACCAGAGCCUGCGCUGACCCACCGUUGGAGCCCCUCGGAGGGGAGCAACCCGGUGCCUGCUGCUUCACCACUGCCGGCCUCAGGACCCUCCCUGGAGGGGCUGCCACCUCUGCCCUCAUCUCCAGGGCCUUGACCUCACUGGACUGUGACUGUCCUCAGGACACCUGCCCCUCCUCACCUAACGGACUGCAGGGCUGAGCAUGUGUCUGAGGUCACACUCUCUGCCCACUCACCUCCUUGGCUGACAUCGGUUGUGUUUGGUGCUGACACUCUGAUCCCGAAGCCAGGGAGCCCCAAGGGGCUGCAUGACCCUGGGGUGCCCCACACAGUUCAGCCCUGCCUGGCAGGGACGCCAGUACUACUGUAACUGCAGCAGGAGCUGCCCGGCCUGCCUUCUGGCCCCACGCCCACAGGCGUAGUCACAUCUUUGUACUGUACUCCCCUGUCUCACCUGGGGCAACCUCAGAGCCCCACUAAGCUGAAGGCCCCCUGGGGGAGGGGGAAGCAUGGUCCUUAUCAUCUGCCCUAUCUUGCCCCUUCCUGUGGAGUGGGCAGAAGGGCUCCCGGGAUCCUCAGAGCUCCCAGGUCUGAGCAGCCAAAGGCCCAGCUGGGCCUCCAGGACCAGCGCGAGCCCCUGCCCCACCCUCCCCUGCCCCAUGUGCCCUGCUUUGUGACCUCUGUUGACCUUCCUGGAAGCAGCCCCAUUACCCUGAGAAUGCGGAGCGCCCUGGCCCACCUCGCCCUGUGUUUCCAGGCCUGCACGUCUGGUCCUUCAGCUGCACAUGGAACUGCAGGGCAGGCUGGCGGGGGGCCUUCAGAUCUCAGAUGAGACUGCACCCCUUCGACCACCCUACUGGGCACCUGCCUCCAGCCCCUGAGAACUCCAUCUUCCCCUAGUUCUGCCCAGGAGCCCCUGAGAACCCCAUCUUCCCCUGGUUCUCUUGCCCACUCCCCUGCUGGGGCUCCUUCCUGGCACUGAGGAGGGGCGCUCCCAAUGCUGUGAGGCAGCGGGGAGGGACCGUGCACCCGUGGCUAUCAGAGCCCCUCCGCUGUCCCACCCUGGGCCUGGGACACGGGCCUGGGGCAGUGUGUGUCUGCUGGUCAUGUGCUGGUGCCAGUUGGGGAGGAAUCAGCUGUCUCGGUGGAUUCUGAGACUCACUGUGGGGCGGGAAGAAGGGUCUUCACUCUGCCAUUCAGGGAUAAAGUUUAAUUUUAUUUUUCUACACAUUUUGCCAGGUCAGGCAUUUUGCUAGUAAGCAGGAUGCCCCCAACUCUCCCUGCCAUGGAGGAUUCUUUUUUUUAAGCUUUGGGUGCUUUUUUAAUACUUUUUUUUUUAAUGUGGGGAAGGAGCUUGCUCUGACGUCACCCUCCUCUCCCCUGACUCCUGUCCUGAGAGCUGUGGAUGCCGCCUCCUGCCCUGCCUACCCCUGAAACGUGGGGAAUGGGGGCCCCAGGACAGCAUCAGGACUUUUGAGUCCAGCUGCCAGCAAUGGUUCCAACUCGGAGGCAGCGCCUCUUGGUCCCCAUUUCUGUAUAGCAGGCGUGUGUGUGUGUGUCGAGGUUUUUUAUUUUUUGCUUAAUCAAACUCCAUUCCCAAAUGCACUCCAUCUCUGGCUCUGAGGGCGCUCCCUCCUCUCAGCCGGGCAGCCUGGCCUCUCCUGCCCAGACCUGCGGUCCCAGCAUCCCCCAGAGCCAGGGAACAGGCCCAGCGGGAGGGGGUUUUAUGUUUUGUUUCAAACAGAAAACACAACCUUAUUUUUCUUUACAAAAGCAAAAAAGGAAACCAAAAAAGAUACAGCCUUUGAAUGAUG